GCGUCCCCUUGGGUCCUUGAUCCUGAGCUGACCGGGUAGCCAUGGCCUUGCGGCUCCUGAAGCUGGCAGCGACGUCCGCGUCCGCCCGGGUCGUGGCGGCGGGCGCCCAGCGCGUGAGAGGAAUUCAUAGCAGUGUGCAGUGCAAACUGCGCUAUGGAAUGUGGCAUUUCCUACUUGGGGAUAAAGCAAGCAAAAGACUGACAGAACGCAGCAGAGUGAUAACUGUAGAUGGCAAUAUAUGUACUGGAAAAGGCAAACUUGCAAAAGAAAUAGCAGAGAAACUAGGCUUCAAGCACUUUCCUGAAGCGGGGAUUCAUUAUCCAGACAGUACCACAGGAGAUGGGAAGCCCCUCGCCACCGACUAUAAUGGCAACUGUAGUUUGGAGAAAUUUUACGAUGAUCCGAGAAGCAAUGAUGGCAACAGUUACCGCCUGCAGUCCUGGUUGUACAGCAGUCGCCUGCUGCAGUACUCAGAUGCCUUGGAGCACUUGCUGACCACAGGACAAGGUGUUGUGUUGGAGCGCUCCAUCUUCAGUGACUUUGUGUUCCUGGAGGCGAUGUACAACCAGGGAUUCAUCCGAAAGCAGUGUGUGGACCACUACAACGAGGUGAAGAGCGUCACCAUCUGCGAUUACCUGCCCCCCCACCUGGUGAUUUACAUCGAUGUGCCCGUUCCAGAGGUCCAGAGGCGGAUUCAGAAGAAAGGAGAUCCACAUGAAAUGAAGAUCACCUCUGCCUAUCUACAGGACAUUGAGAAUGCCUAUAAGAAAACCUUUCUCCCUGAGAUGAGUGAAAAAUGUGAGGUUUUACAAUAUUCUGCAAGGGAAGCUCAAGAUUCAAAAAAGGUGGUAGAGGACAUUGAAUACCUGAAGUUCGAUAAAGGGCCGUGGCUCAAGCAGGACAAUCGCACUUUAUACCACCUGCGAUUACUUUAAGAUACAAACACAGUGGCCUGGGCCUACCUGGAGUCGGGAGCAUCUGUAUCACUGUCUUCCACCUCCACACCUUUCUCACUGGAAGGCCUUCACGGGCAGUAACACGCGUGGAGCUGUCACCUCCUGUGACAAUGAUGCCUUCUUCUGGAUGCCGCCUGAAGGACCUGCCUGAGGCUGUUGUACAGUUACUUUUUUAAAUAAGUAAGAUGAGUACUCUAAAAAUCACGAUGAAAUGUCUAGUAUAGUAAAUAACCUAAAGCAGUAACAUGGUCAUUGAUGAGAAUAUCAGGUAUUCUGUACUGUACAUAAUUGUAUGUGCUGGACUCUUCCACGACUGGCAGUGCAGUAGGUUUGUCAAUGCCACAUCACCGCAGACACGGGAGUCAUGCGCUGAGCCACGGCGCUGUGACAGCUGCUGUGAUAGGAAGUGUUCAGCUCCACUAGAAUCUUGUAGGACCACAUUGUAUAUGUGACCUGUUGUGGAUGGAAACGCCAUGCUGUGCAUAACUGGAAACCGGCAGGAACCUGUCACAUGGUACAAACAACAUGGGUUUCACAGGAAAGCCACGGGAAGGCUCUGUUGUGCACUCUCCAUCAGUAUAACUUUGUGAAUUUGCCGUAACAUUUCCAUUUUCCCAAAAUUCAGCUUUAGCUGCAGCUGUCAGGUUCCUCGUAGGAAACAGAUGGCACAUUUGACCAGAGAACAGAAGAGAGUUACGUAAAGGAACCAUUGAUAAAGAGCAGGGCAGGGUUGAGGGAAGCAACAGGAUGGUGAGACACCCAGGCCAUCCACAGUGGGAAACUGGCAGUUGAGGGCGGGGGCACUGGGUUUUGGAGUCCAGAGCUGCUGCUGCUGCUGCUAUGGAAGAGGCUGUCCAGCAUCAGAUGGAGCCCGAGGGGGAUGGGGAACCCGCAUGCAGGGAACCAGCAGAACAAUCAUCCACCCAGCUGUGCUUGAAGUCAGAGGGCAGUAGAGCCCCUCGGAUGCAAGGAGCCAGCCUCUGGGCACAGAGCACCUUGGAGGAAUGGUAGAGAGGAGAUCUAAAGGGCCAGGUGGAAAACAGCCCCAGACUGUCCACCCAGAGAAUGCAGAGGACGGUCGGCAUUCACCGUUGUUCCCUGUCCAGAAUGAAAACGUGCAUCCCUACGUGAAACAGGGGCAGCCACCAUGUCAUUGUGCGGUGAUGACCAUUCAUAGUCUUGAGUUGGUCACUGCAGGUGUUUUUCAUAUAAAGUAGAGGGAGAAAGAAACAACCUGCCACAGAAUUCCUGGAGUCCCCGCUUCUGUGGUGAGUUCGGAGACCCAAGUUCACUUUGGUAGCUUCCUUGGUUCCCACAGCCUCCUCCCCUCUGCCAGCAGCUCAGCUCCAUGUGGUCCUUACCUGGUGCAGCAUCCUGAGCCUGUGUGCUGUGGGUUGGAGCCUUGGGGGCUCCCUCUGUGGUAGCUGCCUAUCUCUGUUCAGAAUAAGAUUUAUCACAGUGAAUGAGGACAGAUACGCAGACAGAUCAAUACAAAAAAAGACAUGUUGGACUCUGGAGAAAUCCAUGCACAGGCUCUUCCUCCUGUGAGGGACACUGACACAUUGAUUGAGCAACUUUCUCAAGCAGUGAAAAAUACAGUAACAUAUGGGCAGUAUUUCUGCCUGGAAAGCCCUUUAGACACUCACUGCCCGUAAUUUUUACUGGGGGCUGGUCACGUAGGAAUCCUCUGCUUCGCAACUACUCAGGUUCCAGACUCCCAGAAAGAAGGCAGGUGUUCUCCAUAACUCCCAUCGUACCCUGGUAGGGCUGAGUUUGCUGCCCAGCCUCAUUAGCAUGGGGCACUUUUUAGAAGCUGAGUUUCCAGAAGCCAACCAAGGGCCAGCCUCGCAAGGAGGCCCUGCCACAGACAGCAGCAUAGGCCUGCUCUGUGUGUGGCGAAGGAAAGGCUUUCUGAGAGCGCAAGAGCUGUGCUUUUGGCAGAAAAACUUCAGGCAGGGGAGGCAAAUCCGAACCUAGGAGAUGUGGUUUUUUACCUUGGGCAGAGCCUGGGAUUUUAACAGGACUGAGGUUUUGUAAGAGAGGGGCAAGGGAACUGAGCACAGACAAAAUCGCAUGUGAGUAGUGGUGAACCAUGACGCUUAGUCUGGGUAAGGAGGAAAGUGAAGGAGGGAGGGGUGAGGGGACUGAAAUGACAAAGUGGAUGAGAGGCCAAAGGCACACCCUCUUGGAAGAGAAAGUCGGGAACAAAGGUUGAAUAUAGAAUCAAAUCACCUGCGCUUCUGCCACCACAGUGCCAGGAUUAACAGUUGAAUGCAGGUUCUUCCAGUCUUUAAAUAUUUGUGUGUGCAUAUAUUUCUAAAUAUAUCUUGUGUGUAUUUUUGUAUUCUACUUCCAAUAUUUUGAGCAUGUUCCUGUUUUGUUAAACAUUUUAAAAUUUGAUUUUUUCAUGGCUCCCCAUAUAUGCUGCACUUACCAUUGAUUGAGAUGCAAAUCAGGGCUUGGCAAACUGUUUGGCCUGUGGGCCAGAUCCAGCCGUCAGCUGCUAAGAAUGAUCCUUAACGUUUUUAAAGGAUUGGAAGGAAAAGGAAGGAUUAUGUGAUGGAAACUGUAUAUAGCUCUCAAAGCCUGGUAUUUGCUAUCCGGCCAUUUACAGAAAAAGUUUUGACUUCUCCGACACUACAUAAUCUGCAUAAUUUACUGUUUCUUUAAAAUAGAUCUCUUGGAUUAUUUCAGUUUCUUCAUGUUCAUAAUACAGUAAAGAGCAUGUAGUACCCCUUCUUGUUCAAUUUCAGGUUACUUAAGGUAUAAAAGUGGUCAGAGUAUAUGAACGCAUUUUACAGCUAUUGAGUUUUUGCAAAAUGAUUCUCCGGAAUAUGUGUACCAGUAUUCAUACUUGGACCUGGUUCUCUGAAUUUCCCUAUAAAGAAUAUAAUUAAACAAAAUGCAAACAAAAACUUUCGAUUCUGAUACCCAUACAAGUAUUUGUUUUACUUUGCAUUUUAUAAACACUAAACUUCAAUUUAUAUUUUUAUUGGCUAUUUAUUUGCUCUUUGUGAAUUUUCCCUUCAUAUUUAUUAACUUUUUCGAAGAACCUGGUUUUUGUUUUGAUGAUUUAUCCAGUUGUUUUCUGUUUUAUUGAUGUAUACCCUAGUUUUAUUAUUUUUUCUCUGCUUUCUUUAGGCUUCACUUGUUCUUUUUCUAUAGAUUCCUAAGCUUAUUGACUUUAGAUCUUUUUUCUUUUCUAAUAUAGUCAGCCCUUUGUAUCCCUGGGUUCCGCAUCCUUGGAUUCAACCAACCUUGGAUCAAAAAUAUUUGGGAAAAAAGCCAAUAAAAAUAACACAGCAAUAAAAAAAUAAUAAAAAUGUAAAAAUACAGUAUAACAACUAUUUAUAUAGCAUUUACAUUGUAUUAGAUAUUAUAAUACUAUAUUAUUGUAUUACAUUGCAUUAGGUAUUAUACAUACUCUAGAGAUGAUUUAAAGCAGGGGUGUCCAAUCUUUUGGCUUCCCUGGGCCACAUUGGAAGAAGAAGAAUUGUCUUGGACCACACAUAAAAUAACACUGACGAUAGCUGAUGAGUUAAAAAAAAAAAAAGGCAAAAAAACUCACAAUGUUUUAAGAAAGUUUAUGAAUUUAUGUUGGGCUGCAUUCAAAGCUGCCCUGGGCUGAAUACAGCCAUGGGUUGGACAAGCUUCAUUUAAAGUGUGUGGGGAGUGUGUGCAUAGUUUAUAUGCAAAUACUGUAUGAUUUUAUGUAAGGGACUUGAGCAUCCUCAGAUUUUGGUAUUAGUGGUGGUCUGGGAAGGAAGCCCUGGACAACAGAAGAAUGGUUGCAUAUGCAUCAGUGCUGUCAGUUUCCCUGUAGGUGCUGCUUUUGCUGUAUCACACAAAUGUGGAUAAGUUGUAUUUUUAUUUUCGUUCAAAAUGUUUUAAAAAAUAUUUUGAGACUUUUUCUUUGACCCACAUGUUAUUUAGAAGUGUGUUGUUUAAUCUCCAGGCAUGUAGGGAUUUUCUAGGUAUCUUUCUGUUGUUGAUUUCUAGUUUAAUUCUCUUGUGGUCUGAGAAUACACUGUGUAUGAUUUCUCUCCAUUUACAUUUAUUAAGGUUUUCUAUGGCCAGUGUUUCCUAUCUUGAUUAGUGUUCCAAUUCAGCUUGAGAAGAGUGUAGAUUCUGCUGUUGCUGGAGUGUUGUAUAAAUGUCAGAUCGAGCCGAUUGACGGUGGUAUUCAAGUCAUCGGUAUCCUUACUGAUUUUCUCUCUGCUGGGUCCAUCGGUUACUCAGAGUUGGGGUCAUCGGUAUCUUUACUGAUUUUCCCUCUGCUGGAUCUGUUGGUUACUCAGAGUUGGGGUCAUCGGUCUCCUUACGGAUUUUCUCUCUGCUGGAUCUGUCGGUUACUGAGAGUUGGGUUUAAAUUUCCAACAGCGCUGGAUUUGUCUAUUUCUCCCUUGGGUUCUAUUAGUUUUUGCAUCAUAUAUUUUGAGGUACUGUUGUUAGGUACAUAGUUUAUUAUCUUAGGUUAUUAUCUUCUUGAAGAAUUGGCCGCUUUAUCGUUAUGUAAUGCCCCUCUUUUUCGCUGAUGUUUGUCCUUGUUUGAAGUCAGCUCUAUCUGAAUUUAAUAUAGCCACUGCAGCUUUCAAUUAGUGUGGGCAUGGUGUGUCUUUUUUCCUCUUCUAUCUCGAGUCUUUAGUUUUCUUGUAGAUAGUAAGUAGUAAUUGGGUCUUGUGUUUUAAUCUACUCUGACAGUCUCUGUCUUUUAAUUGCUGUAUUUGGACCAUUCAUGUUAGAAGUGAGCGUGAAGAUAAUCAAGUUCCAUUUUACCAUGCUUUUCCCUGUUUUCUGUUUGCUGCAUUUGUUGUUUCUCCCUGCCUCUUUUUCUGCCUUCUCUGGAUUUCAUUGAGCAUUUUAUAAGAUUCUCUUUUAUCUUUUCCCUUAACAUCUUGAUUGUACUUUAAAAAAAUGUUUGUAGUGGUUGCUGUGGAGUUUCCAGUAUACAUUUACAACCCAUCUAGGUCUACUUCGUGAUGGUGCUGCUGCUCCAUGGGGCUGCAGGUACCGACGGCACAGUCUUCUUGGCUCCUCCUGCUGUCACUGUGACAUGGCUGCCAUUCCUUCCACUUUUUUUUUUCUUUGAGACAGGGUCUUGCUCUGUUGCCCAUCGCCCAGGCUGCAGUGGCAUGAUCUUGGCUCACUGCAGCCUCCCCUUCCUGGGUUCCAGCAGUUCUUAUGUAUCAGCCUCCCAAGUAGCUGAUACUACAGGCGUGCACCACCACACCUGGCUAAUUUUUGUAUUUUUAGUAGGAAUGGGGUUUUGCCAUGUUGCCCACCUAGUCACAAACUCCUAAUCUCAAGUGAUCUGCCUGCCCUGGCCUCCCAAAGUGCUGAGAUUACAGACAUGAGUCGCCGCACCCGGCCUCUUCCACUUUUUAUAAGCUAUAAAAUCACUCAAUUCAUUGUUGCUGUUAGUCCAGGAAAGGCCAUUGAUUUUCAGUUUUUUCUUAUUGGAAGGAUGGAAAUUACAGCUUCCAGCCUUCACCCUUUGGAGCUGAAGCUGGAAGUUCCCUCUUUGUUUUUUAAAACUCUGUUAACAUUUUGGACUAGAUGCCUAUAUUUGUGUGUGUGUUUGUAAAUUUACCUAAAUGAUAUACUCUAUUAUUCAAAACUUUGCUUUAAAAAACCUCCACCUUCUCUUUAAACUGCUCUAUUGCAGCGGUCCCAAACCUUUUUGGCACCAGGGACCGGUUUCAUGGAAGGCAGUUUUUACACAGACUGGGGCGGGGAUGGGUGGAUGGUUUCAGCAUGAUUCAAGUGCGUUACAUUUAUUGGGUACUUUAUUUCUCUUAUUAUUACAUUCUUAUAUAUAAUGAAAUAAUUCUACAACUCACCAUGAUGUAAAAUCAGUGGGAGCCCUGAGCUUGUUUUCCUGCAACUAGAUGGUCCCAUCUGGGGGUGAUGGGAGACAGUGACAGAUCAUCAGGCAUUAGAUUCUCAUAAGGAGUGUGCAAACUAGAUCCCUUGUAUGCACAGUUCACAAUAGGGUUUGUGCUCCUGUGAGAAUCUCAUGCUGCCCUGGUCUGACAGCAGGUGGAGCUCAGGCAGUAAUGCGAGCAGGGGAAUCGGCUAUAAAUACAGAUGAAGCUUCACUGGCUUGCUUGCUCACCUCCUGCUGUGUGGCCAGGUUCCUAACAGGUUGCAGAGGUUUGUGGCCCGGAGGCUGGGGACAGGACCCUGCUGAACCGUGUUUUGCUGUUAUGUCUGAAAUCUCAUAGUUAACAGUAGAUGUCAACACAGCGUCUGGAAGGUGUUUCGGAAAUAAUUUGUCUGUUCCACAGCACUUCUGUGGGGCGGGACUCCCUCAUUUUACAAGGAGGAGACCAUGACUCGAGAGCUCGAGCCUGCCAAGGUUGUGUGACUGUGUGGGGCAUCUCACCUCUCGGGCUGCAGGAGCUAGAGCUGCUGCUCUCUGCAUCCUCUGUGUGGUCCUGUGCCCUGGGCCAUCUUGCCUUCCCUCCUGCCGUCUGUUCAGGCUUGAAUCCUGGUGGAACCUUUGACUCCUCUGUCAACCAUAAUCCUAGCUUGAACCCUCCUUUUUCCCUGCUGACCCCCUUAUCCUCCCCAAAGUCACACCCUGCAGGUCAGUGUGCCACUUUCAGUGACUUCUCUCCCUUGUCUCUAACACUGCUGCUCCCCUUGGUGUGUAAUCCCCUGGUUCUUGGUCUCUGCUCCUCUGCCUCUUUAUUUCUUCAUCCCACUCCCACCAGGUUUAUUUUUUUAAAAAGUCACAGUGACCCUGUUUUCUCUUUACUUGAAUCUUUGAGUGGCCUAUCUUCAUUUAGUCAUAGGUCUGAAUUUCCUUUCCCAGAAUUAAUUCAGAAUCCCAGUCUGCCCUGGUUCUGCGUCUUCUACCAGGAUACCAGGCAAUCUGCCAGGCCCUUCUUCCACCACCACCUGCCCAGUAGUUACCUAGAAAUCCUAGCAGUCUUUAAAGCUUGGACGUAAUCACCCUUUUUUCUCCCUGACACCUUCCCUUAACUCUUGUAGGCUGUUACUUAUAUGAAUGUAUAUGGUAUCCUUGUUUGUUAGUAUUAGCUACUGCUGGGCAUCAUAUGACAUCUAACAAACUUACGGAGACAAGGGAUUGUGUCUGACUUGACCUCCCUGUGGUAACAGUGUCAUUUUCUAAACACAGUGUGAAAUGUGUGUUGGUUCGAUUCUGCACCAUUCAUGUAGUUAUUUAGUUAUGUGCUUAUCGGAGCAUAGAGAAGGAUCCUGUAAUUCCCCCAUAGUGUAUCAAUUAUAGCAUUCCGUUGUUUUAAUCUAGCUCACUAUGAAUGGCUUUGUCCUUUUUUCUCCUGGUAUUUUGCCUUUCUUCCUCCCCAAAGAUGUUUCAUAAGUUUACAAUAUCAAUUGUGUUUAUUUUCAUUUGAGUACCAUUUCUCAAUUGAGGGACUCAAGUGAUAAUUAUGACCAAUUUUCUAACAUAAUUAUUGUAAACAUGCCGCUUACCAGUGACAUUCAUUUUAUCCAUAACCUGACCAAAUUAUUGGUUUAGAACAUUUCUGCACCAUCUCAGUUACGUGUUGCCAGUGUCUAAUUAUGUGUAUGUGUAUAGCUAUGCUUGUGCUGAGAGGCAGUAAUUGUAUUUUUCAGUCUUGUUCAUAUCCACAUCCCUAACUGACUGGCGCCUGCUUGGGCUGGUUUCAGUCCAGUCAGGACCUCCGAGGACACGUCAGGCCUCCAGCUGUGCAAGCUCCUCUCAGACCAUCCCUGCUUCUCCAGAGCCCAGACCUUCACACCCACCUUCUUUUUGCUUAAUUGCCAAGAUUUUUACAUGACUCCUGGAGCACGUCUUUUUAACAUGAAAUUUCAGUGCUACAGAAACUGUAGCAUGUGAGUUUGGUUUCAGAAGUACAGUGUUUCAGAUAGAACUUUGCAAUUCAGGAGAAACUGAAAAAUAGGGUUUGGAAAUGUUAUAGGACAAAGUGUUGACAUUCAGUUAAUUGGGAAACAGCUUGAGUCAUAAAACACUAUUUACAAUUUUAUUCUUUUUUCUGUGUUCCUGCCUUACUCUUGUUUUAAAAUACGUGUCCCAGCACCUCAUAUUGUAACCAAGCUCUAGUAUAUUUUAUAUUCUUCUUUAGACAGUGACUUAUGAUAUUAAAAGGAUAUAUUAUCCUCAA